AGACUGCGAUGAAACCCCAGUUUGUUGGGAUCUUGCUCAGCUCCCUGCUAGGGGCUGCCUUGGGAAACCGAAUGCGGUGCUACAACUGUGGUGGAAGCCCCAGCAGUUCUUGCAAAGAGGCCGUGACCACCUGUGGCGAGGGCAGACCCCAGCCAGGCCUGGAACAGAUCAAGCUACCUGGAAACCCCCCAGUGACCUUGAUUCACCAACAUCCAGCCUGCGUCGCAGCCCAUCAUUGCAAUCAAGUGGAGACAGAGUCGGUGGGAGACGUGACUUAUCCAGCCCACAGGGACUGCUACCUGGGAGACCUGUGCAACAGCGCCGUGGCAAGCCAUGUGGCCCCUGCAGGCAUUUUGGCUGCAGCAGCUACCGCCCUGACCUGUCUCUUGCCAGGACUGUGGAGCGGAUAGGGGGAGUAGGAGUAGAGAAGGGAACAAGGGAGCAAGGGAACAAGGGACAUCUGAACAUCUAAUGUGAGAAGAGAAACAUCCUUCUGUGAGUCAUUAAAAUCUAUGAACCACUCUA